AGACUGGAGAGAAGCAGGCCUGAGCCUCCCCAAAGGCAGCUCCUGGGGACUCCCAGGACCACAGGCUGAGACGAGACGCAGGGUGGCUGGAGGAAGUGAGAGGUGAACUCAGCCUGGGACUGGCUGGGCGAGACUCUCCACCUGCUCCCUGGGACCAUCGCCCACCAUGGCUGUGGCCCAGCAGCUGCGGGCCGAGAGUGACUUUGAACAGCUUCCGGAUGAUGUUGCCAUCUCGGCCAACAUUGCUGACAUCGAGGAGAAGAGAGGCUUCACCAGCCACUUUGUUUUCGUCAUCGAGGUGAAGACAAAAGGAGGAUCCAAGUACCUCAUCUACCGCCGCUACCGCCAGUUCCAUGCUUUGCAGAGCAAGCUGGAGGAGCGCUUCGGGCCAGACAGCAAGAGCAGUGCCCUGGCCUGUACCCUGCCCACACUCCCAGCCAAAGUCUACGUGGGUGUGAAACAGGAGAUCGCCGAGAUGCGGAUACCUGCCCUCAACGCCUACAUGAAGAGCCUGCUCAGCCUGCCGGUCUGGGUGCUGAUGGAUGAGGACGUCCGGAUCUUCUUUUACCAGUCGCCCUAUGACUCAGAGCAGGUGCCCCAGGCACUCCGCCGGCUCCGCCCGCGCACCCGGAAAGUCAAGAGCGUGUCCCCACAGGGCAACAGCGUUGACCGCAUGGCAGCUCCGAGAGCAGAGGCUCUAUUUGACUUCACUGGAAACAGCAAACUGGAGCUGAAUUUCAAAGCUGGAGAUGUGAUCUUCCUCCUCAGUCGGAUCAACAAAGACUGGCUGGAGGGCACUGUCCGGGGAGCCACGGGCAUCUUCCCUCUCUCCUUCGUGAAGAUCCUCAAAGACUUCCCUGAGGAGGACGACCCCACCAACUGGCUGCGUUGCUACUACUACGAAGACACCAUCAGCACCAUCAAGUCUGUGGCCUGGGAGGGAGGGGCCUGUCCAGCCUUCCUGCCAUCCCUACGACCACCGCCCCUCACAUCACCUUCUCAUGGGUCCCUCUCCCACUCCAAAGCCCCCAGUGGCUCCCAGAUGAGCCACAAUGCUGUAACAAGCCAUCAACGUCCAGGGUGGCCUGGCCAGCCUCAUUCCCCUUUCCCCCACCCCACACCCCACUUCCAGCCUGAUGCCUCCUUACUCCAGCCUGUCACCCCCUUAGGGACAUCGCGGUGGAGGAAGAUCUCAGCAGCACUCCCCUAUUGAAAGACCUGCUGGAGCUCACAAGGCGGGAGUUCCAGAGAGAGGACAUAGCUCUGAAUUACCGGGACGCUGAGGGGGAUCUGGUUCGGCUGCUGUCGGAUG